GGGGAAGCAGGAGAGGGCCGACCGAGCGCAACAAAGCUGAGCGGCGCGUCGCUUCAGGAACGAAGAAGCCUCGUUAUGCAAGCGAAAAACAAAGAUGCUUUGCAGCCUAUUAAGGAAGACAGGACUGGGAAGGCCCAGGAUGAUGCUUUCUGGCUUCAAUCACUUAUUACGGAUGCAUUCCAUGAUAAAGGAUUUCAGAAAAUAAAAGAAUACUUUCAACAGAAAGAGAGCCACUUUCCUCAAAAAUAUAAUCGUCUUCUAUUAUACCGUCUUGACAGAUCAAUAAAUAAGGAACUAGAUAAAAAUGAAUUUCAGUCUGUGUCACUGUUGCUGAAAUGUAUUCAGCGAUUCCUCGUAGAUGGCCUGAAAGAAGAUGAACCUCUGCUAAUUCGGCAGGGACUGAUCCCAAAGCUAGUUUCCUGGUUUGAAAGAACAACAGGAAUUCUGACCUCGGAAGGCCUAGCCUCAGACACGUCGCUGAUUUGUGUUAUAGAAGAUUUCUUUGACACUGCAUUGAUUAUUUCCAGGAGUAGUAGUGAAGGGAAAAUUCAGAUGUUGGAUUCCUUCCUACUUAGCUUAGGAUUCCUGGUGACAGAAAAGACUGUAAAUCAUUUGCUUCAACAGGAGGGCUUGAAGACUUUUAACUGCAUUUUGCACGCUGUCCCUCGAGAAGAGAGAAAAAAAUUCCCUUUGUCAGAAGGCAUGUGUCAUCUUAUGAAAGACCUUGCAAGGACACUCUUGACUGUGGGUGAUUAUGACCAGCAGGUUGCUAUUUCUGAAGCGCUGUGUAGACUGACGAUUAAAAAAUCAAGGGAUGAACUUGUCCAUAAAUGGUUUGAUGAUGAAGUCAUUGCUGAAGCUUUCAAAGAAAUUAAGGAUCGAGAAUUUGAGACGGACAGUAGACGUUUUCUCAAUCACCUAAACAACAGACUUGGUGACCAAAGAAGGGUGUAUUCAUUUCCGUGUAUUGCUGCUUUUGCUGAUGAGCAUGAGAUGAGAAAACCAGCGGAUGAAAAAUUAGAGAAAUUUUGGAUCGACUUCAACCUAGGAAGUCAGAGUGUCACUUUUUAUAUAGACAAUGCUGAGAAUACUCUAUGGGACUCAGUGACACUUCCGAAGGAAGCGGUGAUGAAUUUCAGCAUAACAGAAACGGAGAAGAUAAAGAUAUUUAUCAUUUACCUGAAGAAGCCCAUGAUUAUCAGCUACAAAGAAGUCAUGAAAAUAGAAAUCCAUUUUGAUUUGCAGUUCAACAUAUCACAAGUUUCCAUUCAAGCUUUAGGAGAAGACAAACAGAUGUUGCCUGACCAGACGAAAAUCUCCUCAGAACUUUUUAGUAAGUCUGAUAAAGAAGACAGGGAGAGUCCCAGUGGCCUUGAAAGAGAAACAGAGCAGGCAGAAGAAUCCACUAACAUGGUGGAGUUUAUGAGUGCUGAAGAUGACCGCUGCCUAAUAACUCUCCACUUAAAUGACCAAUCUGAGCCACCUGUUAUUGGGGAACCUGCCUCUGAUAGUCACCUUCAGCCGGUCCCUCCGUUCGGGGUCCCUGACUUCCCGCAACAACCUAAGUCUCAUUACAGAAAACAUCUCUUCUCUGAGAGUAAUCAAGAUUCAAGUACCAGUGAACUAUCUUGGACCAGUAACCAGAAAAAGAAAUCCCUAAAAUCAUAUUCCAGUAGAAAGAAGACAAGAACCAGAAGUAAUUUGAGAAUCUUGCCAGUUUUCCCUCCCAGUAGUGGCAGUGGCCAUGAGAAAGACCAAGCUAAGCUUCUAUCACCAUCAGAGAAAGAAAUACCCGAGCAAAAUAACACCACAUCUCCAAAGACUUCUGAACAAAAAUUCCAAGAUAGUUUUGCUUUUUUGACUGCUGAAGAUUCUGCCCAGAAAACAGAGCUUCAAGAUCCUCACUCACUGAGUGAGCUCUCUUCCUUGAAGCACUCAGAAGAUGAAGAAAAACCUAAGAUUGUGAACCAAGAAUCACUAACAGAAAGUACUAGCUUGAAACAUAAGCUGAGAAACUUGGAAGACAAAGACAUACCAGAAGGUAGUUUUGCUAAGUCACAACAAUCAAGAUUGGAAGAAGAGGUUGCUCCGGGAUCCCCUUUCUCAAUAACAGAAGAAAGAGAGUUGCCAGAAGGAAUUUCCACUUCAUCCCUAGAAGUUGUGCCAGAGAACUUGAACGGUUCUGCCAUUCUCCCAACCUUUGAAAACUUCACUAAAAAACGGAAAAGAAAAUAUGAGCUUAGGUACAGAAAGCGUCCGUUUAAUUCAGAAAAUGCAAAGAAAGCACCGGAUUGCCUAAUAAAACUUUUAAACCAGAUGCAACUGUUCAGACUCAAUAAACUAGAGCGCUUUCAAAAUUUGGUUCUUCAAGAGUUGAGCAGUCUUAAGCAGGAUAUUCAGGCCCUGGAACACCUUGAGAAGGAGGUUCUGGAAUUCUGGGGGAAACAGUCUGCUGAUCUGCAAUCUUUCUGUGAUCUGCAAGUGCUGAGGUUCAAUUCAACUCAGACUUCAUAAGAAAGCCAAAGCCUGGUUUUAUGAUUGCAGCCCUCAGCCUGGGCUGCCUGAAGACGAAGAGAAAGAGCAAGGUUAUUGUUGGCUCAGGCCUUGUUAGCCAGACUUCGUGCUCUGUACGCAUUCAAUUUCCUCCCCUCCAAACAUCAUCCCUGGGAACUGCUGAGUUCAGAUAGAAUAUAUGUUGGUAGUUUGCAGUUGGGUUAUUAUCCAUUUGUUCAUAAAAAUUAACCUUUUGUAUUAAAAUUUGGUCAGAUAGUAUUAAUAGAAAGUUCAGGAUGUUAAACAACUUGGAGUGGUGUUGCUUUUUUUUUAUAAAAGUAAAAUGGACUUUUUUUUGUUUGAGAAAUGUCUUCAAGUUUUGUGUGAAUAAAACACUUUAGCAGCAUCUGUAUAAA